AGCAAGCAGCUUGGGUCCCUUCCGCGUUGUGGAAGCUUUGUUCUUGGCUCUUCUCAGUAAAACUUGCUGCUGCUCACUCUUUGGGUCUGCACUACUUUUAUGAGCUGUAACACUCACCUGGAGGGUCUGUGGCUUCAUUCCUGAAGUCAGUGAGACCGUGAACCCACCGGGAGGAUCAAACAAUUCCGGACGUGCCAACUUUAAGAGCUGUAACACUCCCUGCGAAGAUUGGAAAGGACUAAAAGAGAAGCAGGACACGACUUAAGAGGGAAGAUAUUCGGGCUGGGCGUGGUGGCUCACGCCUGUAAUUCCAGCACUUUGGGAGGCUGAGGCAGGCGGAUCACUCGAGGAAUAUAUAUGUCCCAGAUGUGAAUCAGGCUUUAUUGAAGAAGUGACAGAUGAUUCCAGAAUCUAAAGUUGAAGGUCCCUUCCACAACCAGGAAAAACUACACAUUUUACAUUUUUUAGGUGGUGGCGGCAGUCGGAUAGACAAUACCACAACAACACAUUUUGCAGAGCUUUGGGGCCAUUUGGAUCACACGAUGUUUUUUCAAGAUUUUAGACCCUUUCUAAGUAGCAGUCCACUGGACCAAGAUAAUAGAGCCAAUGAAAGGGGUCACCAGACUCACACUGACUUCUGGGGAGCAAGACCUCCACGGUUGCCAUUGGGUCGGAGAUACAGAUCUCGAGGAAGUUCUCGUCCUGACAGAUCUCCAGCUAUUGAAGGAAUACUACAACACAUCUUUGCAGGAUUCUUUGCAAAUUCUGCCAUUCCUGGAUCUCCACACCCUUUUUCCUGGAGCGGGAUGCUGCACUCCAACCCUGGGGACUAUGCCUGGGGUCAGACAGGGCUUGAUGCCAUUGUAACCCAGCUUUUAGGACAACUGGAAAACACAGGCCCUCCCCCAGCUGACAAGGAAAAGAUCACAUCUCUUCCAACAGUGACAGUAACUCAGGAACAAGUUGAUAUGGGUUUAGAGUGUCCAGUAUGCAAAGAAGAUUACACAGUUGAAGAGGAAGUCCGGCAGUUACCUUGCAAUCACUUCUUUCACAGCAGUUGUAUUGUGCCGUGGCUAGAACUGCAUGACACAUGUCCUGUAUGUAGGAAGAGCUUAAAUGGUGAGGACUCUACUCGGCAAAGCCAGAGCACUGAGGCCUCUGCAAGCAACAGAUUUAGCAAUGACAGUCAGCUACAUGACCGAUGGACUUUCUGAAGCUAAAGACCACACCUGAAUCAGGGCUGUGGUAAUCAUCUUACCAUAGCUGUAAAUUGUAUCAAAACAAAAAAUUAGUAGAUGGAUUUAGGAAUAUGUAAGAAACUCAACACAUAAUAUAAAUGCAAUGAAUGUUUUUCUUCUUUAAAUUUAAAGUUAGUAUCUACAGAUGGAAUUGUAUCUACAACCAAAUGCCUCUUAUCCCUGAAUUCAGAGUGAUAAUUUUAUAAGUGUGAAACUUAAUUAUGUAGGGCUCCCCCCGUCUGAAUAGAAUUAAUUCCUUAAAGUCUAGUUAGGGUCCUGCUGUCUGUCAUGUUGCCUUGUAACGGAUGUUUCCACCUCCUUCUCCAACCUCUACCCCACCAUUAGUGUAUUUUACUAUAAAAACAGUGGAACCACAGCCCUAAAGUCCUGCUGAUAUAAAGUCCUUUUGUCUUAAUUGUAUUUAAAAAAAAAAAAAACUACUCUUGAUCACAUUAGCUAUGAGGCGAGGUCAAAUUCAGGUAUCUAAGACUAAUGAUUUUGUUUUGUCUUGAUCCCCAGAGAGCAAAUCAAAGAAAAAUUACAGCAAGAAGAGAAAAGUGGUUUAUCAUUGUGUGCUUUGGUUUUCUUAUUUUAAUUUUUUUUGUUUUUUUUUUUUGAGAUGGAGUCUCGCUCUGUCGCCUAGGCUGAAGUGCAGUGGCACGAUCUUGGCUCAUUGCAAACUCUGCCUCCUGAGUUCAAGCGAUUCUCCUACCUCAGCCUCCGGAGUAGCUGGGACCACAGGCAUUUGUUACCAUGCCCAGCUAAUUUUUUGUAUAUUUAGUAGAGAUGGGGUUUCACCGUGUUAGCCAGGAUGGUCUCAAUCUCCUGACCUUGUGCUCCGCCUGCCUCAGCCUCCCAAAGUGCUGGGAUUACAGGCGUGAGCCACUGCGCCUGGCCUCUUAUUUUAAUUUUUAAAGACUACUUCAGUUGAUGCAGUUUCCCAAGAAACCUACAUAACAUAUAUUGGGAGCCUUAUGUUGAUAGGAAUCUGAUUCCCAUUCCUUUUUGGGAAUGAGUUGGGCAGCAUACAGGCACAGAAAGACAGAUGUUUGAGACCUUUGCUUCUGAGAUUUUAAAAAAUGAUUACCGCUGGGCGCGGUGGCUCACGCCUGUAAUCCCAGCACUUUGGGAGGCCGAGGCAGGCGGAUCACAAGGUCAAGAGAUCAAGACCAGCCUGGCCAACAAGGUAAAACCUUGUCUCUACUAAAAAUAUAAAAUUAGCUGGGCGUGGUGGUGCAUGCCUGUAAUCCCAGCUACUCAUGAGGCUGAGGUGGGAGAAUCGCUUGAACCCAGGAGGUGGAGGUUGCGGUGAGCCGGAUCAUACCAAUGCACUCCAGUCUGGGCAACAAGAGCGAAACUCCAUCUCAAAAAAAAAAAAAAAAUCCCCAACUCACUGCUUUUUUUGUUUGUUUCUGUCGCCUAGGCUGGAGUGCAGUGGCACGAUCUCAGCUCACCACAGCCUCGACCUCCCAGGCUCAAGUGAUCCUCCCACCUCAGCCUACCAAGUGGCUGGGACUACAGGCGUGUGCCACCAUGCCUGGGUAAUUUUUGUAUUUUUGUAGAGAUAGGGUUUUGCCGUGUUGCCCAGGCUGGUCUCAAACUCCUGGGCUCAAGUGAUCUGCCUGCCUCAACCUCUCAAAGUGCUCAACUCAUUGUUUACUGUCUUUUUUCCUAGUAAUCUUAAAAUAAUUUGCCUCACAGAAAUAGAGACAGUAAGUGUCUGCAGCCAGUUCACUGUUUUUGGUAAUUCAUUGGUCUUCAGGAGUUAAGAUUUUACAUUGUCACAUUUUAAUUUUUAAGCCUAUUUUUCAUCUCUGAAACUUUCCUUUUCUCCUUGGUUCUGGCUAUACUUGGACUCAAACUGAUCAGUGUGAUCAUGUCCAAAACAGCUUGGCCUGGAAGAGGUAGGCCUUAUUUUUUCAGCCUAGUAGUGUCCCAUGCACAUGCUCUUUGUAGCAUUCAAGUGUUUAACAUUGGAUAAAUUAAGAAGGUCAAGAAUGUUGUUGAAACUUCAAGGUCUCAAAAGGAAAUGAUGGGGACAUAGAACAACUGUUGGUGUACCAAAAAAAGGUACAGAGGGGCACCAUUUGUAUUGUCACACAACAAUGAUCAGAAUGAUCAGUUUAGAAUGAUCAGAACAAAAACACCACUCUUUAAUGGGUCUUUUUCUUGGCUAGAAGUCUUUCCUCAGUUUUUGUUGACUAUCAUACGCUGAUUUGUGGGUGACGGAAGGGGGCUAGAGAUAACGUUUCUCUGUACUUUGGUAAAGGAUGAAGGAGUCAGAGAGGGAACAGAAAAAGUGAGAGAGUGGCCUGCUGAAAUAAUAGCCUGCCUCUAAAAGUUGUGACCAGAAAGUAUGAUUCAUUUGGGCCCAGAGGGAAUAAAAUAUGUUUUUUCAUAUACCUCCCAUAUUACACCUCUGUAGUGAUUGUUUAUUUGGGGAAUGAGAUCUACUUACUGUGCGUUGCCCCUGAAAUGUAGCUUGAGAAUACACACUGGUUUUGAAUUGGGGAGGAGGAUGGAAGGAAAUUAGAGGUGUAUUAUGAAUAUUUGGCCACUACUUAGAUGGAGGAAGGCUAUGUUGAACUUGGGACACAUUGCAGUUUUCAAGUACACAAUAUCAGUUGUCUCAGAAAAAUCAUGACAGCCUGGACAUAUUUGCUUGUCAGUGUCUGGAGAUGCCAGGACAGGCAGUUGUAGUUUUACGUACAGAUAGAGAACCAAUGCCUAGAGAACUAGAAAGGAUCUGAGUACCUUUAAAAAGGGUGGAAACAAAGUACUGGAUAGGGGUCUGCCUUUUUAUACACAGUAUAGCAAACAGCAUCAGACAAAGUUACAUGAAGUUUUCUUCACUUUUUUUGCUCUGGUGGAUAGAGGAUGUGAGACUCAUUUUACUGUUUCCCAGACCUGUCCCACUUAAUGGAUCUGUUGUGUUUCUUCUUAUAAUGGCAGGCACCUCAGAUGUCCAGGUUAAUUUAUGUUGAGGAGUUAGGAUUCUUCAGGGAUUUAUUAUUAUUAUUAUUAUUAUUUAUUUAUUUAUUUAUUUAUUUAUUUAUUUUUUGAGAUGGAGGCUUGCUCUGUCGCCUAGGCUGGAGUGCAGUGGUGCAAUCUCAGCUCACUGCAACCUCCACCUCCUGGGUUCCAGCGAUUCUUCUGCCUUAGCCUCCCAAGCAGCUGGGAUUACAGGCACCUGCCACCAUGCCCAGCUAAUUUUUUAUAUGUUUAGUAGAGACAAGGUUUUACCUUGUUGGCCAGGCUGGUCUUGAACUCUAGACCUCAGGUGAUCUGCCAGUCGUGGCCUCCCAAAGUGCUGGGAUUACAGACGGGAGCCACCAUGCCCAGCCUGAGAUUUAUUAUAAGGAAUUGGUUCACACAAUAAUGGAGUUUGAGAAAUCCCAAGAUCUGCAGUGGGCCAGCUAGAGAUCCAGGAGAGCUGAUGGUGUAGUUCCAGUCUGAAGGCCAGCUUGGAUACCCUAGAAGAGCUGAUGUUUCUGUUCCAGUUCAGAGGCAGGAAAAGACUGAGGUCUUAGUUCAAGCAGUCAGGCAGGAGGACUUCUCCCUUACUUGUUCUAUUCAGACCUUCAACUGAUUGGAUGAGGGCCACUUACAUUAGGGAGGGCCAUGUGCUGUAUUCAGUCUACUGACUGAAAUGUUAGUCUCUUCCAAAAACACCUUCACAGACACACCCAGAAUACUGUAUGACCAAAUAUCUGGGCAUCAUGUGGCCUAGUCAAGUUGACACAUAAGAUUAACCAUCACAAUGAGGAAAAACAGAAAUGAUACAUGUAUACAGAGUGCUCCUCAUCCCAAUUAAGUUUCACCAAGUUAAUAAUGUGUCUCUAUGAGAAGUGGUUCACCAUGUUGGUCAGGCUGUUUUCAAACUCCUGACCUCAAGUGACCACCCGCCUCGGCCUCCCAAAGUGCUGGGAUUACAGGUGUGAGCUAGCACUCCCAGCCGACAGGUGCUUCUUAAAUGUUUUCUUUGAGCAGGAAUUGGUCCAGGAAUUGGUUCUCAAGUUAGAAGGAAAAUUUGAGGGGAAGAACUUGUUUUUUCUCCAAUCAGUCUCUGAUUAAAUAGUUAUUAGGAAAAACUCCUUGCUUAUGUCUUUGUAUUGCACAUUUUUAUAUAUGUAUAUAUGUGUAAAUAGAGAUAUUUAUAUAUUCACAGACAAACACGUGUAUGCACAUUUCACAAUGGAGGAAGAAGGGAUAUGGUGUGCACUGAGGUAAAGUGAGCAGGGAUACAGAAGAGAGCUGGAGCCUCACAGUCUGAUUCUCUCAUUGUACAUAACCUUUAGGGUCUUUGUUUCCCUGAGUUCUCUGGUAUGGGGCACUGUUGGCUUGGGCUGGUACCCUGUUAUUCUCUGUGAUGAAGGGAUUCACUGGAGGUAAAAACGUAAUCAUUUCCAAAGGUUGAGAAUAAAUGACUUUGAGGAAAGGGUGUUCAUUAUCCGUUGCUUCUAUAUUAUAAUCAGUUGAACUACAAUACGGUUAUCUAUUGAUUUUUUUUAAUUUUUCUGACAAAUUAUUGACACCAAAUUGAAUAAUUCAUGACCUGCAUGCUUCAGCUUCUUUCUCCCUGGUUUCCAGGUGCUAUUCCCUCAAGAAAUGCAAAUUAAAUAUGUCGGUCUUAAUAAAUCAGGAGGGAAGCAUAGUCUGUGUCUGUUUUAAAUGACAACAACAACAAAACAGCUUUGGGGUUUAAGAAGUGGAAGACACAUUUUUAUUUUUUUGAGACACAAUCUCACUCUUUCGCCCAGGCUGGAGUGCAGUGGCGUGAUCUCAGGUCACUGCAACCUCCCGCUCCUGGGUUCAAGCGAUUCUCUUGCCUCAGCCUCCCAAGUAGCUGGGAUUACAGGCACGUGCCACCAUGCCCAGCUAAUUUUUGUAUUUUUAGUAGAGAUGGGGUUUUGCCAUGUUGCCCAGGCUGGUCUCGAACUCCUGAUGUCAAGUGAUCACCGACCUCAGCAUCCCAAAGUGCUGGGAUUACAGGCAUUAGCCACCACGCCCAGGUGAGAAGACAGAUUUUAAGAGAAGGAGCAGGGCUGGUAUCUGAAUAGGUAUUUGGAUGUUAGGGGAAAACCCUUUUUGGCCUCUGUGGUAGAGCGAUCGGAAGGUAAAAGUGCUGUUUACAAGAAUAAUCCAUUGGAGAUCUGGGGAUUGGGGACGACUUAUAGGAUAGAGUCCUCUUGUUGAGAAUUUCCCGAAUGAAUCUCAUGUAGGUUCUGUCACAGUAAGAUGGAGGAAAACUUUGAUGGGGUAAGUAUCACAAGUGGCUGUCCUAUAGGGGGAAAUCCUAGCCUGCAGUAAUGUCAGUGUCUCAGUAUUCAGCCAGCGAGCCACUGAGCUGCUCCAGGGGUUUAAAAUAGAAUGCAUAGAAUACAAUGUAUACAGCUGGUGAUGCUUUCCAGGAUCAAAAUAGAGCCCUUGUCUGAUCCCAUUGACAUUGUAAGGUUUCGAUCUCUCAUACCUGCCACAGACAAGUACAUUGUAGGCAUUCAACUUUUAAGGUUUUAUACAUGCAAACUUUAUGUUUUCCUGCCACACUACACUUGGUGUCCACAGAAGUGUAGUUUGUAUGUUGCCUCUUCUUCCUCUUUCAACCAGAACACUUAGAUCUGUGAUCAUAGGAUGUAAGCCUGUGAUUCUUUACUUUUUCUAAUAAGAAAUACAAUUUUCAAGAUCCAAAAAUUAUUAGAUUCUUGGCUGGGCAUUGUGGCUCAUGCCUGUAAUCUCAGCAUUUUGGAAGGCUGAGGCAGGCAGAUCACUUGAGGUCAGGAGUUUGAGACCAGCCUGGGCAGCACAAUAAAACACCAUGUCUACUAAAAAUACAAAAAUUAGCCAGGUGUGGUGGCAUGCACCUGUAGUCCCAGCUACUUGGGAGGCUGAGGAGGGAGAAUCGUUUGAACCAAGGAGGCAGAGGUUGUAGUGAGCCAAGAUUGUGCCACUGCACUCCAGGGCAACAGAGAGAGACCCUGUCUCAAAACAAAAACCCCCAAAUUAUUAGAUUCCCUUCCAACAACUUGAUAGCCAUAUUAUUAGUAUUUUUGAUUAAAGAAUACAUAACAAAAAGCUGCUAUGAUUUCAGUAAUGCUUUUAAGUUAAUUUAUUAGUCACACCAGAAUCUACAUCCAAUUGAAAUAUAUACAAAUAUUUGAAAGAUAUUUAUUCAGGCUGAAGAUUAUGGUAUAUAGAUUCCUUCUGAUAACCUCAUGGCCUCACAGGUUCAAAACCCGUGUUUGUGAAUCACUCAUACAGAUUGGGGCUAAGAUGCGUGUCCAGAAAACCACCUAUUAUGCAUGAAAAUUUGUAGGCUUAUUUGAAGGCAAUUGUAUCAACACAUUUUGAAAGCCAAGACACAAGUAUUUUAAGUUUCUGUUUAACCAAGUCUCGAGAUAAGCAGAGUAAAUAAACUCUUUAGAAGCAAGACUCAGUUGGUAUGUACAAAGUGGGAUUGCUUUGUAUAUAUUCCGCUUAGUUUGAGUCAGAGCUAGUAAUCUGAUGCUCUUAAAUGUCUUCAUAAACUUGGGCAGUGAUGUUUCCUUUCUGUGAUUAUGUGUCACAGAUUUUUAUAUGUGGACUAUAAUUAGUAUAGUACAAUGGCUGAAACUUUUCCUAUAGUUGGAUAUAUCUUCUGAGACUUCCAGUGAUUGUAUAAUGUUGAGUAGCUCCAGAAGAUUAUUUGAAUAGUAAAAACAAAAGACAUCUCUACCUAUGUGAGUUUAUUAUUUAGUUAGAAACACAGAACUAACUAUUUAAAACAGGUAGAGAAAGAUUAAGAUGAAUGUGAUGUAGUGGAGAAAGCUUUGGAGACUUUGGAGUCAGAACUCAAAUGGCUCUAGGUCCCAAAUCCAGACUCUCAUUUUGAUUCUCAGAACAAUUCUGUGGAAAGAGAAGAUACAAUAGGCAAUAUCCCUUUUUACAGAUAGGUAAACAGAAAUAGCAUCUCAAAACCUCAUUUGCACUGGGUGAGGUGGCUCACGCCUGUAAUCCCAGCACUUUGGGAGGCUGAGGCGGGUGGAUCACUUGAGGUCAGGAGUUUGAGACCAGCCUGGCCAACAUGGUGAAACCCCGUCUCUACCAAAAACACAAAAAUUAGCCAGGCAUGGUGGUGCAUGCCUGUAAUCCCAGCUACUUGGGAGACUGAGGCAGGAGAAUUGCUUGAACCCGGGAGGUGGAGGUUGCAGUGAGCUGAGAUCAUGCCACUGCACUCCAGCCUGGGCAACAGAGUGAGACUCCGUCUCAAAAAAAAAAAAAAAAAAUUCAUUUGCCCAAUGACAAAUAGCUGGUAUGUUGCAGAGCCAGAAUUUGAAUCCAGGUCUUUUUGCCUCCAUGGCUAGUCCUUUUAUCUCCAUGGGAUACAGUCUAAAAUCCUUAGUUUGAGGUUCAAGACUAUCACUAAUAAGAGUCUUACUCAUCUACUUCAGCCAUAUCUCUUUCCGUUCCCACAAACCUUAGCUCCCACAUUUGGCAGGUCCUUGCCAAGGAGCACAGGUAAAGUGUCUCUUUCCUUUUAAUGGCUCACCAUGGAGCUGUAGCUAAAUUUCUGUGCUCUUACCCCUUUAUUCAUGUAGUUCCUCCUAUCAGGAAUAUCCUGCCCACUCUCUGCUUAACUAUGACAAGAGGUCAUCUGUCCAAAGAGAAAGAAGAGAGUUUGUGGAUUUAGGAGAAAAGAAAAGACUCCAAAUACUGCUAUGGGCAUUUAUUUAAAAAGAGAAAUGACCAAAGAGGUUAACAAGUAUUUAGAUGAAGCUGGGCAGUUGUAGUCUGUGGUGCUCUUGGUCUGCACAAAUCUUCCUCUUCCUCCAGCAGUGCUGUAUGGAUGUUGUUGAAUGUUGAGGUCUGUCUGCAUUUUCUCAUUUUCAUGCCAAGUCAAUCACUGGAUCUGGCUGUCUUCCUUUCUGUCCUACCUAUCUUUGCUUGUUUUCUCUCUCUUUCCUUUGCAGUGUUAAAUAAAAAUUUAUUCCCCCAAAA